GCCUCCGGGGCUGCCCCUUGCCCGGUGUUGGGGUCUGGUCGGUUCGUGCGGAGCCCGCGGGCCCGCGGCGGUUUACUAGCAGCUGACGAGCUUGCCUGUCCAUCCAGCUGACUUGGAAUUAGGGUCUGUUCUUCAUUUCGCACCCUCACCUACACCGUGACCCGAACACUCUUUUCCUUUGUUUUUAUUUUUGCUUUAGUCUUCAUGUUGCCAGUAUCAGCAGUUCUGCGGUGUGGCCAGUGGAUAGAAAUUAGUUGUUUUGCUCUAUUUUGCUUUGUUUUCAGGCUUUUAAUAACCAGAGCUCUGAGUGGGUAGAGCUUCGGGGCAUUUAAUUUUGAUGCGUUUCAGAUCCCCAAAACAUAUGCUAGCGAGUCCCCUGUCCCCCGUACUUCUCUCCCCUUCACUCUUAGUGCCUACUUGACAUUCGAGCCUUUCUUGUUUCUUUCUUCUGUCCCCCCGCGAUAAAUCCACUGGGACAGAAAGGAGAAAAACGUGAACUUUCUGGCUGCCCUGCUUGGGCUUGGUCCGAACCUUCUAGGCAUCAGGGCAGGAGAGGGAAGCCCAAUUUAGUCUCAAGAACAAGACGCGCGCUUCCAGUUAGCUUUUCUUAGUUAAUUAAGUUGAUAAACGCCAAUCUUCUUGGUCUAUUUGUUUCCUACUUGUUUCAGAACCCCGGGGAAGAGAUAGCAUGAUUAUUUGGCACUUUGAAGCACUAACUGGAAAUUAACUCCUCCCCCUAUAGUUAAGAAGUAUAUAUCUGGAGGGGUGUGUGUGUGUGUUUAACCUCUCCCCAGUUUAAUGGGAACAGAUUAUCCCUGUGGAGCUUCUGUGAGUUAUAGUCCUAAAUCCCUUUUACUGAUCGUCCCGUACAGCUUUUAUCUAGUAUUCCUGAAUGUGUAGUUGACUCAUGGCUCAACAGUCAAUUAAAAAUGGGAUAACACUGACUAUAACUUACAGAAAUGCUAACUAUAUCUGUGCAUCAUCCAAUAAUUCUUGUUCUCAUUUCUUUUUUUUUUUUUUACUGUCGUUCAUGAUGAUUUUUUAUUUCUAAAUGACUAGAUGGUUAACUGAAAGCUAGAUUCAGUAUGUUAAUGUCAUUUAACACCAGCUGGAAACCAGAUUAAAAGGGUCAGAUUUUAGUGUCUGGAUUCUGUGGGAAUUUUUGUAAGAAUUUCUAAGCAUGGUCUGUGCUUGUAAGACAUCCUGAAGAAGGAAUCGUCAAUGUUUGAAGAAUUAAAUAAUGUUAUUCAUCUAUUGCUACUGCAUAAGUUAUACCAAAACAUAGUAGCUUAAAACAACAGUAAACAUUUAUUACUCCACAGUUUCUGUGGGUCAGGAACUCAGAAAUGACUUUCUGGGUUGAUCUGGCUUUGGGUCUCCUGAGGUUGCAGUGAAGAUAUGUGCCAGGGCUGCUGUCAUGUCACUUGAUUAGGGGUGCAGGAUCAUCAGCUUCAAAGCUUUUCAGGAUGUCCAGCAAAGAAUCCUGUGGGAAAAAAGAGACAUCUCAGAGGAAAGACACCACCACCUCAUCACCCAAUUUUGGUGAAAAAGACAAGAAAGAGAGAAAAACCCCAGCAAGUUCUACUAGUUCAUCUUCUAUAAGAUCAGUUUCAUCAGAAAAGAGAAAACUGAAAUCAGAUCAUACAGAUGUUCUGUACUAUAAUAUAAAAAGAAGACAAGGACUGAAAAGAUUGAGUGUAGAAAUUGACACUCUCAGAAGGAGACCAAAAAUCGGUUCUUCAUCCCAAAGACCUAUUAAACUCAAAGAAGCAUCAUAUUCAAAUGAUAAUCAAAUUAUUUUGCAGAGUCCUUCUUCAAAUGGAACUAAAAAAGACAUACAUAAAUGUGUAGACUUUAAACCUAAAGAUAUCAAAUUGACAAAUGCUGGGAGCAAGCUUGACCAUGGAAUUAAAAGCCUUAGUAGUCCUAAGAUUGCCAGUGAUGUGAAACCUAAAGCCGAAGGCCAGGCAAGUGAAAAUAAAUGGUCUCAUUUACUUGUUCAGAGAGAGAAGAUGAAAGAACUCAAGAAAGGAAGAAACAGUAAAUUUAGAGACAAUUCUGAAAAAUGUGUCUUAGAGAAAUGGAAGAGAAAUCAAUUUUCUCAGGAUUAUAACUCCAACAAGAUAAUUAAGGAACCCUUGGGAUCUAGAAGACAGAAGAUCAGUUUCAAAAUCCCUAUAAAAUCCCGUGACACCCUCCAGAAACUUGUAGAAGAAAAUGUCUUCAACAUAGAUUCUAAUAAUUCGAAGACUAAGCAGGAAGAAAGAGAAUACCUGGAAAGCUCCCAGGUUUCAUUAAAUGUGACUAGGCAGAAAACUGAACAUUUACUUUCAGAUUUUACAUAUAAGCGGACUGUUCAUGAGUGGAAACGAAAACAUCAUUAUGACCAUCAAGAAAGUAAUGAUUCACAUUCUAGGGAAAACCUAACCCAGAGUUUUGAAGCACCAUGUUGUUCCGUGUCAUCUGAAAGUAUCCAGGAUGCAGAUCAAGAGAUGCAGAUAGUAGAAGAGCUUCAUGCUGCACGUGUGGGAAAAAGUGUGGAUUUACCUGGAGAGUUAAUGAGUAUGGAAAUUGACUUAGAAGAUGAUGUACAUUCCUCCUCUGCAAAUAAUACUUCAGACAGAAAGCUUCUAAUUGUUAUUGACACAAAUAUUCUGAUGAAUCAUCUCAAAUUUGUUAGAAUUUUGAAGACAACAGAAGUACCAGGUUUUGACAAACUUGUGUUAAUAAUUCCCUGGGUCGUUAUGCAAGAGCUAGAUCGUAUGAAGGAAGGAAAACUACUAAAACGUGCCCAGCACAAAGCUAUACCUGCAGUUCAUUUCAUCAACGACAGUCUCAAAAAUCAAGAUAGAAAGCUAUGGGGUCAGUCAAUACAACUUGCAUCCCAAAAACAUUAUGGAUUGAGUGAUGAGAACAAUGAUGAUCGAGUACUAAAAUGCUGUCUCCAGCACCAGGAAUUAUUCCCUUGUUCUUUUGUUAUUCUGUGCACGGAUGAUAGAAACUUAAGAAACAAAGGCCUAAUAAGUGGUGUGAAGUCACUCAGUAAAGAAGAAUUGAGUGCAGAGUUAUUACACUUAUCUCUGAACACAGAUGUGUGUCAUCAGCCUUGUAUUCCUAAGCAACAGUUGAAAGCAGAAACAACACCCUUGAAAGAGAGCUAUAAGGAGGAAUCUACAAAUUCUGGACUGUCCAUUCUGCUUGAGAGCAUUGUAUCUGAUCUUGAAAAAUCUCUUGGAACAGGUUUAUCUUCAAUAUUAGAAACAGAAAUGAAAAUUGCUUUUGGAAACCUUUGGAUGGAGAUCCUGUACCUGAAACCACCAUGGACUCUACUACAUUUACUACAGUGCUUUAAAAAACAUUGGUUGGCUGUAUUUGGAUUAGUUAUGGAAAAGAACUUGCUUUUAACUAUUGAGAGCCUAUACAAAAAUCUCCGUAAAGCUAAUAAGGCAGUGGAUUUUACAACAGUCAAAUUCUUGCUUCAGGAUUCUAGAAGUUUGUUACAUGCUUUCAGUACAAGGUCAAAUUAUGAUGGUAUUCUUCCACAGACCUUUGCUCAAGUAAACAACCUCCUUCAGACAUUUGCAGAGGUCAAGACAAAACUUAAGCCAAAUUCUUCAGAAAACACAGUGACUAAAAAGCAGGAAGGUACUUCAUUGAAGAAUUCUCAUAAUCAAGAAAUCACUGUUUUCUCGAGUUCUCAUCUUCCCCAACCCAGCAGGCAUCAAGAAAUCUGGUCUAUCCUAGAGAGUGUUUGGAUUACAAUAUAUCAGAACAGCACGGAUGUAUUUCAAAGAUUGGGCUCAAAUUCAGCUCUGACUACUUCAAAUAUAGCAUCAUUUGAAGAAGCAUUUAUAUGUCUUCAAAAGUUAAUGGCAGCUGUGAGGGAUAUUCUUGAAGGAAUUCAAAGGAUUUUGGCCCCAAACAGUAAUUAUCAAGAUGUUGAGACCCUCUAUAACUUCCUAAUCAAGUAUGAGGUAAAUAAAAAUGUCAAAUUUACUGCCCAGGAAAUUUAUGAUUGUGUUUCUCAGACUGAGUAUAGGGAAAAGUUAACCAUUGGAUGCCGCCAGCUGGUUGAGAUGGAAUAUACCAUGCAGCAGUGCAAUGCAUCUGUUUAUAUGGAGGCCAAAAACAGGGGAUGGUGUGAAGACAUGCUCAACUAUAGGAUAUAAGUACUGAUUUGUAACUUUAAAGGAAUUGCAUUUGUCCUUAAGAAUAACAGAGUAGUUUUCAAUCUGGUCACUCUUUUGGGCCAAACCCAAGAGAAUUUUAAGAAAUGUUUCAUAGGUAUAAAAAGGUGAUCGCCUAUUACUGACAGUCUCAUUGUAGCUCUAAAAAGCCUAAUGUAUCCACUGUGGAAUAAACUCCAUAGACUCAACUCUUCUGGAGUUCACAAUGCCUCCCUACCUCUAUUCUUGAUAGUGAGCCAGUAUCUCUAAGGAAAGGAGAGCCGUAUUUUUAGUCAUCCUAGGGCAGGAGCCACUGUGGCAUCUGAGGAAGACCCAGGGUACAGUAUUAGCAUUUCUUUCAACCCUAAGUAUGGGCAUGUGACCAGAGACACUGCCAAACCCUAAGAAAUCAUUAGGGCAUGAUCAUGCUCACCAUAUUUCACAAAUGAAAUCUUAAUGUGGGCUGUUUUUUAUGAUCAAACUGUCAUCCAUGUUGACCUGAUGAAAAUAACACCCUCCUUCACCUCCCUCAGGGUAAUGAAAGUAGAAAUUUGACUGAAGCUCCUACUUCCUUAUACAGCCUUUCCUUCUGUGGGCUUGUCACUUUUCAGUACAUUUCUAGUGGGGAAGAGCAGGGCGACCCCUCUGCUGGGUUUCUCCUUAAAUGUGAAGCAAAAUAAAUUUAUAUAAUGGAAUUUGGUGGCAGUGACUGAUGUUUGUCUCUAGCUAAAACCAACUGUUUAGUUGACUUUUUAGUUAUAGGAUAAGUUGGAAGUCCUUGUUUACUGGAAUAUAUUAUGCUUUUGUUAACACAUUAGAUUAAAUAGAAUUUGGUAUUCUAUUAUAAAUGUUUAUUUUUUAAAGCAAUAAAUAACUUAUUUUUGGUAAGAUUUGGCUUUUUACUUCCAAAUUGUUUCUGAUAUGUACAUAAGGUAUGAUUAUAAAAGUGACUGUCUGCAAUAAAAGAGAACUUGUUCAGGA